AGUACGCGACGCGAGGACGCAGGAGGAGGAGCCCGGAGCUGCAGCCACCGGGGAGCCAGGUACCUUCCGCGAGACGUCGAGGGGCGAGUCCUAGUCUCUUUUCUCCGCACUGGAAGACUUGAACACUUCCUUCUCUGGUCUCUGUCACCCAGGCUGGAGUGUAGUGGCGCAAUCUCAGCUGGCUGGAGCCUUGACCUCCUUGGGCUCAAGCUAUCCUCCCACCUCAGCCUCUCAAAUAGCUGGGACUACAGGCAGCAAAGCACCUGCUCUGAGUGGCCAUGGGGAAGCGAUACUUCUGUGACUACUGCGACCGCUCCUUCCAGGACAACCUCCACAACCGCAAGAAGCACCUGAACGGGCUGCAGCACCUCAAGGCCAAGAAGGUCUGGUACGACAUGUUCCGAGAUGCAGCUGCCAUCUUGCUGGAUGAGCAGAACAAGCGGCCCUGCAGGAAGUUUCUACUGACAGGCCAGUGCGACUUUGGCUCCAACUGCAGAUUUUCCCACAUGUCAGAGCGAGACCUGCAGGAGCUGAGCAUCCAGGUGGAGGAGGAGAGGCGAGCCAGGGAGUGGCUACUAGAUGCUCCUGAGCUCCCCGAGGGCCAUCUGGAGGACUGGCUGGAGAAGAGAGCCAAGCGGCUGAGCUCAGCCCCAAGUAGCAGGGCUGAACCCAUCAGAACCACUGUCUUCCAGUACCCCGUGGGCUGGCCACCAGUUCAGGAGCUGCCUCCAUCCCUGCGGGCACCCCCACCUGGGGGGUGGCCUCUGCAGCCCAGAGUCCAGUGGGGCUGAGCCCCUUGCCCCCGACUGACCCCCACGUGGUCACUUUUCUCAUCAGUCACAAUAGGAAGCCAAGCCCGGUUCCUGCUACGCCCCAUGGAGGCUCCGAGACCAUCUGCCCAGCCUCACUGAGGCUCAGGACACGGCCACACCAAGUGCAGCCCUCGUCCUGGGUCUGCACCGGGCAGCUCUCCCCUCACUCUCCUCCACCUGCCCCCCUGCUUCUUAAGAAGAUGGGGGAGAAAACUUCCAAAUGUUUAUAAAGAAAGUCUGUCACCACA